CUAGCUGUACCUCAUUAUCUAUCCCAGUGCCUGGCCUGUGAUAUCCCUAGAAAUUAUUAUUGCACUAAACUAAAUUAAACACAAAGACUUAGUUAGCGGAUUCACAAUUUUUAGUUGUACUACAUAGUCAAACGAGUAGACGUUCAGGUCACAAAAUCUAGCCUGUCUCCCCAUGAAACCACAAUGCCAUUGUCUGAACAGAUUAAAUAAAGCAGAGCAUCACCUCAAACGAUUUUCAUGGUUCAAAUCUAGGUAGCUAUACUUACCAGCUGUGAGGCUUAGGCCAACCUAUUAACCUUCUAUUUCACUUUUCUGCUAAAUGAGACAAUAUGGACUUGACUUCAUUUUGUGAGAAAUAAAUAAUCUAAGUAACUGGUCAAACACAUUUUGUGCUUCUUAAAAAAAGGUGGUACACACACACACACACACACACAACACCCGAUAUAAUACAAUAUUUUCAAAUGACACUAGAAAUAUUUUAGUCAGGUCUAAAGGAACAGAAGUUAAUGAUAAAAUGAUAAACAAUAAAUAAUAGCUACUGUUUCAUGAGAAAAUUACACACAUCUUACUUGACUUAAACCUCACAACAGAAUUGAGCAGAAAGUUAUUACCCUGAGAAAGGGGACUUAAGGUUGGCAGGAUAACAAGUGGGAGAAUCUAGAGGUAAAGUCAUAUCUAUCUUAUUGGAAACACUCAAGAACGUCAAAUAAGCAUGAGAAUUUGAGCAAGACUGAAGGAGAACGUUUAAGUUCCCUUUCCAACUCAUAUCCCAAUUCUGGAAUCUAAUUUCUGUAACAAGUAACUAUAUUCCUUACUACAGAAGUAAAGAUGGCCCCAUGGAGAAACUGGCAGCAUGGCAUGAUGGAAAUGGAAUAGAAUCAGGAAUUGUUUUGUACCUGUGUGUGUGUGACUUUGGUGUUCUGACUCAGACACAUAUUUGAGAGGUAGAGAGGGGAGAAGAGGGUUGCCACAUUAUGUAACAGAAAGGAGCCCACUGCUUAAACACUUACCUUGUGCCAGACAUUGCACUAGGACUUUAUUACCUGCAACCCAUCCUGCAAAACUGUGAAGAUUUGAUAUGAUCAUUCUCAUUUUAUGGUUGAGAAACAAGGGUUAAGGACAUUAAAAAUUUACUCAAUGUUUAAACAUUUGCCUGUCUUAUUCUAAAGCCCCUUCUCUUUUCACAAUCCCUUUAAGAAAUGGACAUCCAAUAUUUGAGUGGCAGAGGCAAAAACAUGGCCUACCAGAACCAUUAUGAUAGCUUUACAAUAUGCCCACCAAUUAUUUGAUAGUCCUCCUGCCAAAUGGUGAAGGCUAAUUACCCUCCUACAGAAUGUGACUCACUUCUAAUGAAUAAAAUAUGGCACAAGUAAAAGUGUGCGAUUUCAGAGACUAGGUCAUAAAGAACGCAGUGGCUUCUUCCCUGCUCUCUCUUUCUUAGGUCAUUCUCUCUGGGUGAAUCCAGCUGACAUGUUGUGAGGACACUCAAGCAGCUUUAUGGAAAAGCCCACAUGGUGAGCAACUGAGGCCUCCUACCAACAGCCAACAAGAAACCGGGGCCUUUGCCAACAGCCAAGAAAUAAGAAUCAGAAAGAAGGACACACCAUUCCAUAGCACAGAACACAAGUAGAUGGCUCCCAUGAAGAAUCUAGCAUCAUGGUAUGGCAGAAGCAGAAUGGACUCAGGAAUCAUGGUGCCUACACUGGAAUUUCAGAUCGGCCACUGACACAAUGGACACAUUAUUCAACAUUUCCAAAUCUUGGCAUUCUUAUCCACAAAGUGAAGAUAAUAAUUGUCAAUUCACAGGUGAUUAUGAUUUAAAGAGAUUACUUUUGAAGAGUUCCUAACACAUUCAGUCAACAUUUAAUGAUGCUUCAGGCACUGUGUUCAUUGCUAGUGAGCGUAUGACACACACAGCCAUACGGUCACAGAGCUUUCAAUGAAAAGUAACAUAAUUGCUCAUUUCACCAGGCCCCCGGCUUGGGGCGCCUUCCUUCCCCAUGGCGGGACACCUGGCUUCGGAUUUCGCCUUCUCGCCCCCUCCAGGCGGUGGGGGUGAUGGGCCAUGGGGGGCGGAGCCGGGCUGGGUUGAUCCUCUGACCUGGCUAAGCUUCCAAGGCCCUCCUGGAGGGCCAGGAAUCGGGCCGGGGGUUGGGCCAGGCUCUGAGGUGUGGGGGAUUCCCCCUUGCCCCCCGCCGUAUGAGUUAUGUGGGGGGAUGGCGUACUGUGGGCCUCAGGUUGGAGUGGGGCUAGUGCCCCAAGGCGGCUUGGAGACCUCUCAGCCUGAGAGCGAAGCAGGAGUCGGGGUGGAGAGCAACUCCAAUGGGGCCUCCCCGGAACCCUGCACCGUCCCCCCUGGUGCCGUGAAGCUGGAGAAGGAGAAGCUAGAGCAAAACCCGGAGAAGUCCCAGGACAUCAAAGCUCUGCAGAAAGAACUCGAGCAAUUUGCCAAGCUCCUGAAGCAGAAGAGGAUCACCCUGGGAUAUACACAGGCCGAUGUGGGGCUCAUCCUGGGGGUUCUAUUUGGGAAGGUGUUCAGCCAAAAGACCAUCUGCCGCUUUGAGGCUCUGCAGCUUAGCUUCAAGAACAUGUGUAAGCUGCGGCCCUUGCUGCAGAAGUGGGUGGAGGAAGCUGACAACAAUGAAAAUCUUCAGGAGAUAUGCAAAGCAGAAACCCUCAUGCAGGCCCGAAAGAGAAAGCGAACCAGUAUCGAGAACCGAGUGAGAGGCAACCUGGAGAAUUUGUUCCUGCAGUGCCCGAAACCCACACUGCAGAUCAGCCACAUCGCCCAGCAGCUUGGGCUCGAGAAGGAUGUGGUCCGAGUGUGGUUCUGUAACCGGCGCCAGAAGGGCAAGCGAUCAAGCAGCGACUAUGCACAACGAGAGGAUUUUGAGGCUGCUGGGUCUCCUUUCUCAGGGGGACCAGUGUCCUUUCCUCCGGCCCCAGGGCCCCAUUUUGGUACCCCAGGCUAUGGGAGCCCUCACUUCACUGCACUGUACUCCUCAGUCCCUUUCCCUGAGGGGGAAGUCUUUCCCCCAGUCUCCGUCAUCACUCUGGGCUCUCCCAUGCAUUCAAACUGAGGUGCCUGCCCUUCUAGGAAUGGGGAACAGGGGAGGGGAGGAGCUAGGGAAAGAGAACCUGGAGUUUGUGGCAGGGCUUUUGGGAUUAAGUUCUUCAUUCACUAAGGAAGGAAUUGGGAACACUAAGGGUGGGGGCAGGGGAGUUUGGGGCAACUGGUUGGAGGGAAGGUGAAGUUCAAUGAUGCUCUUGAUUUUAAUCCCACAUCAUGUAUCACUUUUUUCUUAAAUAAAGAAGCCUGGGACACAGUAAAAAAAAAAAAAAAAGAAAGAAAAGAAAA